AACUUCUCUCAGGAGGAAUGGGAAUAUCUGGAUUCUGCUCAGAGGAACUUGUACUGGGAUGUGAUGAUGGAGAACUACAGCAACUUACUCUCACUGGGUCUACAUUGAGACAGAUAUCGGUACAAUGGUGACCAAGACCAAUACAGACCCUGCUCUCAUGGAAUUGACAUACUAGUUCUUGAGAUGUAUAAUAAACAAGUAAACAGAUAAGUAGAGAACAUAUAUAGUGAUAUGUAUAAGAAUAAAGGGAUGGUGUGUGAUGGAGAAAGAGCUAAUUCAGACAGUGUGGUCAGAAACCAAUCUCUGUGGUCUUAAUUUGGCAUUUUAUAGAUACACAGUUCCUUUUCAGUGGUUCACCUAAUGUUUUUGCAAUUGGAAGUCCUCAUUGGAAUCAGUGUGUUUCAAUUUGUCAUUCCUUUUAUAUAUUAGUUGCUGUCAUGUUCUUUGGUAAACUUUUGUAAUUCUAGUAGGAAAGGCAAAGAGGCUUUUUUUAUUAUAUGUCUUUUAUAUUACUGUAAGUAAGUAGCCACCUCAAAUGGUGCACUAGAAAUUUUCAUACCUUCUAUUAAGUCUCAUUAUGUUUAUUGAUUUUAUUGGUUCAGUAUACAUUAGCCCACCAGAGUCUGAUUUUUGAUGUCCAGCUGUAUGAAUAUUGGAUGAAAUUUUGAUAUACUGAUACCAUGUUUCUUAUGGUGAUUUCUGUGUGCUUUGGCUUUAUCCUUUAACCUUUGAAUUUAUUCUCACUUUUUGUCCAAAGCUUAUCCAAGGCUCAUUCCAUACCCUCCCUAUCCCAGACCCAGCAUUGAAUUGGAUAUGAGUGCAUUUUUCUGGUUUUGUUUAGUUUAGCAUGUUUCAGUACAUAAACUUUUUUCCCCUCAUUUGACUCUUGUAUUGUCAAAAUGGUGGCACUUUAGCUCCCGCAAACUAUUUUUGUGUCCCUUUGAUGUGACCCACUGUUGUAAAACUUUUUUCUUUCUGGCAAAACAUUACAGGUUACAUCUCAUACCUCCCCUGGUCCAGAUCAUGAUUCAGGUCUUUGUUCUAGGAUUCCUGGCUUAUUAUCUGGUUUAUUUCAAUAACAAGGACAAUAAGUCAUGGUUAUGAUUUUUCUGUUUCAUGGAGUGAGUGAACAUUUUAUCUCAUUCCAGGAAUUUGUUUUUUUCCAACUAUUGUUGCUUUUUGGGUUGGUUUUAAAUAUUCCUUUACCAAGAAAUUCAUUCAUUAGUCUACAUUUUCAGCUUUAUUAGCAUAGGAGUCUUAAUAACAUUUUGUGUAUGUUUUCAUCACCUAGUGAUUGUUUGCUAAUUCCUCACCUUUUCUUUAGGUCACUGUUCUUUAUACAUUGGUUAUUUUUACUUUUUUAAAAAAAAGCAUUUAAGUUUUUACUUUUUAUGAGACAAAUGUAUUUGCGUUCCAUAGAUGUCAGUUAGAAAUGUUUUCAACAUCAUGGUUCUCUACAAACUUUGUGAUUUCAGUUACAUUUCCACAUUGACUCAACAGUUAUUUAAUAGUGAGCUUCUUUUUUUUUUAAGACGUAGUCUCACUCUGUUGCCCAGCCUGGAGUGUGGUGGCGCAGUCUCAGCUCACUGCAACCUCCGUCUCCCAGGUUUGAGCGAUUCUCCUGCCUCAGCCUCCCAAGUAGCUGGGAUUACAGGCAUGUGCCACCGUGCCUAGCUAAGUUUUUUUGUAUUUUUAGUACAGACGGGGUUUCGCCAUGUUGGCCAGGCUGUUCUCAAACUACUGACCUCAAGUGAUCCGCACACCUUGGCCUCUCAAAAUGCUGGGAUUACAGAUGUUACAGCCACUGCACCCAGCCUAGUAGAGAGCUUCUUUAUUUCUAACUGAAACUUCUUUUGAUUUACUGAUACUGGCACUCAAAUCUGGUUUUAAUGUUGUCGUCAGAUAUUGAUGCCUGCAUUAUUUCAUCUUAUACAUAAUUAAGUCACAGAAAAUUAUUCUUGCCCUUUAUCAUGCAGUGUUUAUGUGUUGCUCUGAGUUUUCCUCAGGCAUUCCCUUCUCUCACUGUUGGCCUCCAGAUGAUCUCCAUAAAAUCCUUUGCUACAAAGUGCCUUCCAAUCUUGUCUACCUAGACCACCUUCUUCAUAUGAUUCUGUUAGCAUAUUCUCCUUUUCACACAUAAGCCCUUGCUCAGAACUGUGUAAGUCUAACAGUAGUUAUAAUUAUAUUCAGAUAUUAUUUUAAUAUCUGAAAUAUAUUUUUGGAAAGUACAGCAUUAGUUGACUUUUGCUAUAAGAAAAUGGAAAGGAAUAUCUGUAAAAGAAGAUAAAAGAAAAAAUAGAGGAAGGUUUUAGGAGGACGGCGGAGUAAAUGUAAAUAUGCUGUUGAAGAGAAGUAAAUAACACAUCCCGAUUGUAUUUCUUCAUUCCACAUGUCAAUCAUGGCUCUGCAUAAGAGGGAAUAAGCAAUAGUGGUGGACAAUAUGUGUAGGUGGAGAAGCAGUUGGAAAAUAAAUACAUAUGAAUGUUCGCCAUAUUUAUGUAUCUUACUGUAUUAUAAAUAUACAUAUGUAAUCACUAAUACAAUGUGAGGGUUGGGAGGCAUUGGUAACUGGCAUUAUUCUUAUAGUUACAUAAUUAUUUUGAUAAUUAUUGUUUUCUAGUGACUUAUCUUUGUAUAUAUACUUUUAUUUUUAUUUAGAUUCAUUCAUACAGUGAUUUACUUUUCCUCUAAUUAAUUAUCAUAUACUAUGUCCUUAGGUCUUGUUAUACAUUGGCACAUGAAAAUUUAUUACAUUUGUCCUUGUGGAAUUUAAGGAAUAAGGAAGUAAAUGGUGUAAGAGAAAAGUAUUGAAUACACAACUGAAAAAAAUAUAUAUGAGGAUUUGGAGUCCAGGAAUGAGACUAAGCAUUUAUCUGUAGGAAAAGAUAUUAUUCAAAACACUGGUUCUCAGUGGGAGGUAAUGGAAAGUAGCAAGUUAUGUGGCCUUGAAGGUUCCAUUUUCAGAAAUGACUGGCAAAGCAAAAGCAAGAUUGACUUACAAGGACCUGAAGUGGGAUAUUUCAGUCAAAUGAAAAUCAUCUCUGAAAAUGUGCCCAGUUACAAAACUCAUGAAUCUCUUACUUUACCUCGGAGAACUCAUGACAGUGAGAAGCCCUAUGAAUACAAGGAAUAUGAGAAGGUCUUCAGUUGUGACUUAGAGUUUGAUGAAUAUCAGAAAAUACAUACUGGUGGAAAAAACUAUGAAUGUAAUCAAUGUUGGAAAACCUUUGGGAUAGAUAACUCCAGUAUGUUACAACUGAAUAUUCAUACUGGUGUGAAACCUUGUAAAUAUAUGGAAUAUGGGAAUACAUGUAGUUUUUAUAAAGACUUUAAUGUAUACCAGAAAAUUCAUAAUGAGAAGUUCUAUAAAUGUAAGGAAUACAGAAGGACCUUUGAAAGAGUUGGAAAAGUUACUCCACUUCAAAGAGUUCAUGAUGGUGAGAAACACUUUGAAUGCUCAUUCUGUGGGAAAUCCUUUAGAGUGCAUGCACAACUUACUCGACAUCAGAAAAUCCAUACUGAUGAGAAAACUUACAAAUGUAUGGAAUGUGGCAAGGACUUCAGAUUUCAUUCACAGCUUACCGAACAUCAGAGAAUUCAUACUGGUGAGAAACCCUACAAAUGUAUGCACUGUGAGAAGGUUUUUAGAAUUAGUUCACAGCUCAUUGAACAUCAGAGAAUUCACACUGGUGAGAAACCUUAUGCAUGUAAGGAAUGUGGGAAGGCUUUUGGAGUAUGUAGAGAACUUGCUCGUCAUCAGAGAAUUCAUACUGGUAAGAAACCCUAUGAAUGCAAAGCAUGUGGAAAGGUCUUUAGAAAUAGUUCAUCCCUGACUAGACAUCAGAGGAUUCAUACUGGUGAAAAACCCUAUAAAUGUAAAGAAUGUGAGAAAGCAUUUGGAGUAGGUAGUGAACUUACUCGACAUGAAAGAAUUCACAGUGGUCAAAAACCUUAUGAAUGUAAGGAGUGUGGAAAGUUCUUUAGACUUACGUCAGCCCUUAUUCAACAUCAAAGAAUUCAUAGUGGUGAGAAACCUUAUGAAUGUAAGGUAUGUGGGAAGGCCUUUAGACAUAGUUCAGCCCUUACAGAACAUCAGAGAAUUCAUACUGGAGAAAAACCCUAUGAAUGCAAGGCAUGUGGGAAGGCCUUUAGACAUAGUUCAUCCUUUACCAAACAUCAGCGCAUUCAUACUGAUGAUAAACCCUAUGAAUGUAAGGAGUGUGGGAAUUCCUUUAGUGUUGUUGGGCAUCUUACUUGCCAACCGAAAAUUUACACUGGUGAGAAAUCAUUUGACUGAAAUAAAUGUAUAAAGUGGUUUUUUAUUUCUGAUUUUCACAGGAAAAUACUGUGGAUGGAUUUAAUAGGUAAUCAAGGCAAUUCAGUAUCUCCCUCUCUUAAAGUCUGUUUUUAGACUUCAUGGUCAUUCUGUAUGUAGACGUAGAAUUGCUUAGUCAUAGCUGAUAUAUACUUAUAGCUUUGUUAGAUGUUGCCAAAUAUUUCUCCUUUUUAUGUUAAAAAGUUUUUUUCAUGAGUUUCUCAUCCUGGCAUGUUUUGUUUACAAUAGCUUUUGAUGUUUGUAUUAUUGCUCUUUUGACUAUUCAGUUUUUUAAUUGUAAUAUUACUUCAAUAUCUUUUCUGCAUUGUAAUUCUUUGCUUGUGAUAUCUAUACUUACUUAUUUUCCUCCACAGAGUUAGCACUCCUAGUCAGAUACAAUGUAUUUUUACAGUCUUACAGCUCAUCAUUUUGUGUAAUGUUGUUUUGUUUUGUUUUAAAUGAUAGAAGUGUGAUCUCCUUUCCAUUUUCAUCCAAUUGUUGACUUCUCUUUAAAUUUCUACUUUAUUUUGAUACAACAUAUUCCCCCCAAAAAAACACAUACAUAGGAACUGGUUAUAUUCCACCAUAACACACACACACACACACACACACUAUAUACAUAUAGUGUAUAUACACAUAUAGUGUAUAUAGUGUAUGUGUGAUGUAUACUAUACAUAUCACAUAUACUAUAUGUGUGUAUAUAGUGUGUGAUGUAUAUGUGUGUGAUGUAUACUAUAUAUGCCCACACAUGCACUACAUAACACACUAUAUAUAUAUAUAUAUAUACACACACACACACACAAUAUAUGUAUAUAUAGUAUAUACACUAUAUACUGGGCACUAUAUAUAUAUAGUGUGUAUGUGUGUUAUAUUGGAAUAUAACCAGUUCCUUUAAGCAGUCUUUUUACCUGCAGGCUAUACCAACCAGGAUCCAAAUGAAGAGAACUCUUUUAAAUAUUUGAUAAAACUACUCACCCAGUAAGUCUCUUAAAAUUUAUCAUUCUCUUAAAGUAUCACUCUAAAAUUUGUCAAACACCUUUAAAAGGGGAGAAAAAAUGACCACUGAACUUACAUUAAGAGAAUUUACAACUAUAUAUUAACAUGGCUUCAAUUGUUUUUUUAAUCUAUUAUCAUUAUUUUUCUUUUUAUUCCCUCUCAGAGUUGACUUACUAGGUUUGGGCAUUUCAACAAUCAGCAGACCUUCUUUGGUUUAACUAAUCUCAUUUAACUCCAAAAUCAUCUCUCUCUUAGGACUGCUGACUUGGUUAUGCAGUCAAUGAGAUCACGAGCCACUGGUUAUUGGAUUUUUUUUCUUUUUUUUUAGACAGAGUUUUGCUCUUGUUGCCUAGGCUGGAGUGCAGUGGCGCAGUCUUGGCUCACCUCAACCUCUGCCUCCCAGGUUCAGGCUAUUCUCCUGCUCAGCCUCCUGAUUAGCUGGGAUUACAGGCAUGCGCCACCAUGACCGGCUAAUUUUAUAUUUUUAGUAGAGACGGGAUAUCUCCGUGUUGGUCAGUCUGGUCUCAAACUCCCGACCUCAGGUGAUCCACCCGCCUCAGCCUCCCAAAGUGCUGGGAUUACAGGCAUGAGCCACCGCACCCAGCCUGGUUAUUGGAUUUAUUUAUUUAUUUUGAGAUAGAGCCUUGCUCUGUCACCAGGCCGGAGUGCAGUGGUGUCAUCUCAGAUCACUGCAACCUCCACCUCCCAGGUUCAAGCGAUUCCCCUGCCUCAGCCUGCCAAGUAGCUGGGAUUACAGGCAUGCGCCACCAUGCCCAGCUAAUUGUAUUUUAGUAGAUAUGGAGUUUCACCACGUUGGCCAAGACAGUCUCGAUUUCCUGACCUUGUGAUCCCCCUGCCUCGGCCUCCCAAAGUGCUGGGAUUACAGGCAUGAGCCACCACGCCUGUCCGGUUAUUUGAUUUUUAUAAGAAAAUUUUACUAUUAUUUUCAGAUAAAUUUAUGUCACUGUCAUUCAUUACAUUUUAAUUUUUGAAACUGAUGUCUUUCCCAGAAUUUAUGUACUCUAUAACGGUGUGAAUGAUUACCAGUAUUAAGCCAUUUUCUCAUCUGAUAUAUUGAGCUAUGUUUUAUGUAAGUAUUGCUUAUUCAAGUAGUUUUAAAAGAUAUGUAAUUGGUUGUUGUUUCAUGUCCUACACAGUAAGAACAAGAGUAUGUUAACCUUUUUGUCAGGAUAUUUGCUAUUUCAUAUCUUUGAAAUAGAGUAGUAGCUCUAUUUCUAACUAAAUUCUAUUUAUGUAACAACACAGCUAAUUUACUCUUGGAUCUCAUUCUCCCUUUUUAUCCUGAGUUACCAUCAGUGCUAAUGUUCCUCUUUUGGGUAUAGUUCUCCAGGAGAACUUGUCCUAUAUUUCUUUGUGUGUGUUUUUUUCCUUCCAGCUUAAACAAAUUAAAACUAAAUAUCUAAACCUUGUAUACAGACAUUAAAAUUAGUGAGAGAAACAAAAUAUCCUUGUGUCUUGGCUUUUACUUUUUGAAGUCAUUAACAAAUAAUAAAUUAAUGAAUAAAAUGUGUCCUUAUUAUGUUUUCCUUGUUUGUAGUUACAGCUAUAUUUUUAUCAUAUUAACAUUUUUCACUUAACUUCGUAAUGAACUUAUGGCAUUUCACACUUACUCGAAACCAUAAUAUAAUUAUUAUUGGUGGUAUUACUGUUUGGUUUUUACUAUUUUUACUCAAAAACAUAAAACUUCACCAUUCUUUCCAUUUUCAUUUGCCCCUUUAUUCUUUCUGACUUUUCUCUAAGCCUGCAUAGGAGCUUUAUUCUCAUAUUCAAUAGGAUAGGAUAUUGCAGUCUCAUCCUGUUUUCUGCUGUCCUGCACCAUUAAAUUUUAUAUGUCCUUGAAGGAAUUCAAUUUAAUGGCAACUAAUAUAUGUAUGUUAGGGACAGGUAAAGAGUCUGUGACUGAGAUUUCUGGAGUUAUAUAACCCCUGCGCCACCCCCCACCCCAACUCCAACUUGCCAGAAUUCACCCCUUAACCUGCAAUGUGAUUGUAUUUGGACAUAGGGCAAUGAGGACAUAAGAAUGUGAUUCUAAUUUGAUACAAAUGGUGAUCUUAUGAGAAGAGGAAGGAGAGACGUCUCUUCCUAUGCUCACACACAAAGGAAAGUCCACAUGAGGACACAAGGAGAAGCCAAGAGAGCCCUUACCAGGAAUUAAACCUGCUAAUCCCUAUUUUAAUUAGAACAGUGAGAAAAUAAAUAUCUGUAUUUAAGCCUCACA